GGAAUUUACCUUUGUACUUCACACGGUCAGGGUUGGUGGUGACUACGUGGGUCUGGAGCUGACUGCCGUCCUGACACGUCCUAGAGCUGCAAGCAGGUCCUGCCAGAGAGCCACCAUGACCUCUCAGCCUCUCAGGCUAGCAGAAGAGUAUGGCCCAAGUCCUGGGGAGUCUGAACUGGCUGUGAACCCCUUUGAUGGGCUUCCCUUCUCUUCCCGCUACUAUGAGCUGCUGAAGCAGCGCCAAGCCUUGCCCAUCUGGGCUGCUCGCUUUACCUUCUUGGAGCAGUUGGAGAGUAACCCCACUGGAGUGGUGCUGGUGUCUGGGGAGCCUGGUUCUGGCAAGAGCACCCAGAUCCCUCAGUGGUGUGCAGAGUUUGCGCUGGCCAGAGGGUUCCAGAAAGGACAGGUUACUGUUACUCAGCCCUACCCUCUUGCAGCCCGGAGCCUGGCUCUGCGGGUUGCUGAUGAGAUGGACCUGACCCUGGGUCAUGAGGUUGGAUACAGCAUCCCCCAGGAGGACUGCACGGGGCCCAACACCCUGCUCAGGUUCUGCUGGGACAGGCUGCUUCUGCAGGAGGUGGCCUCGACCCGAGGCACUGGAGCCUGGGGCGUGCUGGUACUAGAUGAGGCUCAGGAGCGGUCGGUGGCAUCAGAUUCACUCCAGGGGCUACUGCAAGAUGCCAGGCUGGAAAAACUUCCGGGGGACCUCAGAGUGGUUGUGGUUACUGACCCAGCCCUUGAACCUAAGCUCCGAGCUUUCUGGGGCAAUCCUCCUAUUGUGCAUAUACCCAGAGAGCCUGGUGAGAGACCUUCCCCCAUCUACUGGGACACCAUCCCACCUGAUCGGGUGGAAGCUGCCUGCCAAGCAGUGCUUGAAUUGUGUCGGAAGGAGCUUCCAGGAGAUGUGCUAGUGUUCCUGCCCAGUGAGGAGGAAAUUUCCCUGUGCUGUGAAUCCUUGUCCAGGGAGGUAGAGUCCUUGCUUCUCCAAGGGCUUCCACCACGAGUACUGCCCCUUCACCCAGACUGUGGACGAGCCGUUCAGGCUGUGUAUGAGGACAUGGAUGCCCGAAAGGUUGUGGUCACUCACUGGCUGGCUGACUUCUCCUUCUCCCUCCCUUCCAUCCAACAUGUCAUCGACUCAGGACUGGAGCUCCGAAGUGUUUACAAUCCUAGGAUCCGAGCAGAAUUCCAAGUGUUGAGGCCAAUCAGCAAGUGUCAGGCAGAGGCAAGACGAUUGCGAGCAAGAGGGUUCCCACCAGGAUCCUGCCUCUGCCUGUAUCCUAAGUCCUUCUUAGAACUAGAAGCUCCACCAUUGCCACAACCCAGGGUGUGUGAGGAGAAUCUGAGCUCCCUGGUGUUACUACUAAAAAGGAGACAGAUUGCAGAGCCAGGGGAGUGUCACUUCCUGGACCAGCCUGCUCCAGAAGCACUGAUGCAAGCCCUGGAAGAUUUAGACUAUCUGGCAGCCCUGGAUGAUGAUGGGGACCUGUCAGAUCUGGGUGUCAUACUAUCAGAAUUCCCUCUGGCCCCUGAGCUGGCCAAAGCCCUGCUGGCCUCAUGCGAGUUUGACUGUGUGGACGAGAUGCUCACCCUGGCUGCCAUGCUCACAGCUGCCCCUGGGUUUACCCGUCCUCCACUCAGUGCAGAAGAAGCUGCCCUGCGUCGGGCCCUGGAACACACGGAUGGUGACCACAGUUCUCUGAUCCAGGUGUAUGAAGCCUUUAUACAAAGUGGAGCAGAUGAGGCUUGGUGCCAGGCUCGAGGUCUGAAUUGGGCAGCAUUGUGCCAAGCCCAUAAACUUCGGGGAGAACUCCUAGAACUCAUGCAACGAAUUGAACUUCCCUUGUCCCUACCAGCCUUUGGCUCUGAGCAGAAUCGCAGAGACCUUCAGAAAGCACUGGUGUCAGGAUACUUUCUCAAGGUGGCCAGAGACACAGACGGGACUGGAAAUUACCUUCUCCUAACCCAUAAGCAUGUGGCCCAGCUCUCCUCAUACUGCUGCUACCGAAGCCGCAGAGCUCCUGCCAGACCCCCACCAUGGGUGCUCUACCACAAUUUCACCAUAUCCAAAGACAACUGCCUUUCCAUUGUUUCUGAGAUUCAACCACAGAUGCUGGUGGAAUUGGCCCCUCCAUACUUCCUGAGUAACUUGCCUCCCAGUGAGAGCAGAGACCUUCUGAACCAGCUAAGGGAAGGAAUGGCAGAUUCUACAGCAGGGAGCAAAUCAUCCUCAGCCCAGGAGUUCAGAGAUCCCUGUGUCCUGCAGUGACCUGCCUGCCUAUGGAAUGGAGCUGGGUUCAUCUCAUCACAUUAGAUUAUCCCUCAGGGUGACACCAAAGCACCCAGACAGAUUUAGAAGCCCAAAGUUUAGGGUCAAAUGUAAACCCUGGAACCUGAGUCCCAAGAAAUGGUAGACUGGGAAUGGAAAGAAUGGGGUAAACCACAGUCUACAUAGGGAAGGACUCUUUCCUUAGCCUUCUCUUAUUGAUUGGAGAGGGACUGACAUGCUCCUCAUUCUCUUAACUUUGCCAAACCCAUUCUUGUACUCCCUUGUGAUCUAUAAAAGAUUUUUCUAUGAUGCCAA